AGUUGUUCUCAGGUGUUUGGGCUUGUUGUUCCGUAUACUCAGUGGGUUCGCGGCCGCCGGCCCAGUGAGGCUGGGUUCGAGGAGCUGGAGCGGGAAACUGGAGCUUAAAUUCUGGCGGCGAGAUGGACAUUCUGAAAUCAGAGAUCCUUCGGAAGCGGCAGCUGGUGGAGGACAGGAACCUGCUGGUGGAAAAUAAAAAAUAUUUCAAGCGUAGUGAGCUCGCCAAAAAAGAAGAGGAAGCAUAUUUUGAAAGAUGUGGCUACAAGAUACAGCCAAAAGAGGAGGACCAGAAACCAUUAACUUCAUCGAAUCCAGUGUUAGAACUUGAACUGGCAGAGGAAAAAUUACCUAUGACGCUUUCUAGGCAAGAGGUCAUCAGAAGAUUGAGAGAAAGAGGAGAACCAAUCAGACUAUUUGGAGAGACUGAUUAUGAUGCUUUUCAACGUUUAAGGAAAAUAGAGAUCCUCACACCAGAAGUUAACAAGGGAUUGAGGAAUGAUUUGAAAGCAGCCUUGGAUAAGAUUGAUCAGCAGUACCUCAAUGAAAUCGUCGGCGGUCAGGAGCCUGGAGAGGAAGACACACAGAAUGAUCUGAAAGUUCAUGAGGAAAACACCACAAUUGAAGAGUUAGAGGCGCUUGGAGAGUCCUUAGGGAAAGGCGAUGAUCAUAAAGACAUGGACAUCAUCACCAAAUUCCUGAAGUUUCUUCUUGGCGUUUGGGCUAAAGAAUUGAAUGCCAGAGAAGAUUAUGUGAAACGCAGUGUGCAGGGUAAACUGAACAGUGCGACCCAGAAACAGACCGAGUCCUACCUAAGACCACUUUUUAGAAAGCUACGGAAAAGGAAUCUUCCUGCUGAUAUUAAAGAAUCAAUAACGGAUAUUAUUAAAUUCAUGUUGCAGAGAGAAUACGUGAAGGCAAAUGAUGCUUAUCUUCAGAUGGCCAUUGGAAAUGCGCCUUGGCCCAUCGGUGUCACUAUGGUUGGUAUCCAUGCCAGAACUGGCAGAGAAAAGAUUUUUUCCAAGCAUGUUGCACAUGUUUUAAAUGACGAAACUCAGCGGAAAUAUAUUCAGGGAUUGAAGAGGUUAAUGACCAUUUGCCAGAAACACUUUCCUACAGACCCAUCCAAAUGUGUGGAGUACAAUGCACUGUGAGAUCUGUGUAUGGUGUGUUAAUAACAAUAAGAAACUUAGGGAAGCAGGCUGUGGACUUCUGGAAUUACCAACAGGAAUGAGGAAAGAAGAAAACUGGAGUUUCCAGUCUCUGAGUUCUACCUGAUGUAACUCUUGAUUGGUUUUAAGAACUUUGUUGGCCUUCAUUUCAUAUCUGACUGCAAGCUGAUUUUUCUUUCUUGCUUUCAUUUUAAUUAGUCCAAAAUUAAGUUUUAAAGAUUUUUCCUCACAAUUUAAAUCCAUAGACAACAGAAGGGGGUUUAAAAUGACCUUUUUUUCAGUUGACCCGAAAGUUGUGGUUAGAUGAUUAAAAAGAAACAUUUGAGGAUGGACUUAAUUAUUUCAGUAAAAUAUUAUAAUUUGCCUAUUGUCUUUUAUGUAAUAUUUAUAUAAAAUAUUUUUAUAUAUUUCAAAAACAUGGGACCAUUGAAUGAAACUUUAUAGUCCUUAAAUGUUGCUGAACUUUUGCUGUCUUGCAAUAGAAUUUGAAUGUAAAUAUUAUUACUGGUAUAACUCAAAUGUUAUUUUUCUUGCAUUUCAAAGCUUGCUUUUAUCUUCCAAGAAGUGUAAAUUUUAGUAUUUGUCAUCUCUCAGGACAGAUACAAUUAAUAGGAAAUAGAAGUUUGAAGAAACAGAGAUGGCACAUCAUAGCAAACUAAGUUCAAAACAGAAUAACCCCAGUGCAUCAAGGUUAAGGUGGGACAGUGGUUUGUGAUGCCAGGGAGAGUGGGGAAAUUGUGAUGAUGCUGGUAGACCUGGGCAGACUGUGUUCCCAGCCACACCCGCCAACAGAGGAGGAAGGUGCUGGUACUGAUGUCCCCACCCGAGAGUCUGUCCUGGCCUUGGUUUUCCACAGUGAGGGCUCGUUCUAAUGUUGCACAAUGUCAUACUCAGAUAUCACUGUGACCUGUUACUAUGCUUUAGAACCCGAGAGGCCUCUGUUCACAUGGCAGCAUGUGUGAGUGGAUGCUCCCGGAGCAGGUGGAGUGGUGGCGCUGGAUAGCGGUAAGAGCGGGGGCUCCAAAGGCAGAACUUCCAGCUUCACAUCUCAGCUCUGCACCUGCUCGCUGUAUGACUUUAGCAAGCAACUGGAUCUUUCUAAGCGUCAGCUUCGUUGUCUUAAAUGGUAGUUGGUAAUAAUAGUCCAUGCUUCGUAGCAUCACUUUUGUGUUCAAGCAGAAUGCUGAGCACACUGGCAAAUAAUAAGAGCUCGUAAAUAUUAGUUGUUGUGUCACUGUUGUCAUUAGAGGGAAGCCAGAGUCCCUUUCAGGAGCCCUGUGUUUAGGGGCAGUGUGUCCUCACAAAACAAUAACAGUAAUAAUGAUGGUGUUAGCAGCAACAGCAGUAAUCAUGGAAACGUUGAUUAAGCAUUUACUGUAUCUGAACCCUGCGGCUGUUCCUGCUUUCAGCCACUUCUGCAUUGAGAAGGGCCGGGGAUGUGGUGGAAGCUAGAUGUCACCAAGUAGGGGGAUGUAGAUUCACAGCGGUCUAUUCUGGUUCCUCUUGGGAGGUUCAAACCUUGGGGAGGUUCAAAAGCCAGUUUUGGCCACUUGUGCUCUUCUGCUGUGCCUAGACAGGAUCGUUUCUGAUGGUUAUAUGCAUGGUGGUGGCUGAGGUCCGCUGUCUGGAAUUGAAUUGGGGUUCCUUGCCUCCCACUCCCUCAUUUGGAAACCUUUUCUUGUUAUUAAAUCAGUUAGAGGGGGCCAGGCGCGGUGGCUCACGCCUGUAAUCCCAGCACUUUGGGAGGCCGAGGUGGGCAGAUCACGAGGUCAGGAGGUAGAGACCAUUCUGGCUAACACUGUGAAACCCUGUCUCUACUAAAAAUACAAAAAAUUAGCCGGGCAUGGUGGCGGGUGCCUGUAGUCCCAGCUACUCGGGAGGCUGAGGCAGGAGAAUGGCGUGAACCCAGGAGGCAGAGCUUGCAGUGAGCCGAGAUCGUGCCACUGCACUCCAGCCUGGGCAACAGAGUGAGACUCUGUCCCCUCCCCCCCGCAAAAAAAAAUCAGUUAGAGCUUAGUGUAACUUACCAGCGCAAGUGAGAGACAGACUUUCGUAAGAUAUGACAGCAAUCUAGAUUUUUUAUAUAGGACCUAUUUAUAAAUAUUGUUGAAUGAGUACUCUCCGAGUUACUUUUUCUGUAUUCACCAUCAGGUCACACAGUAGAGUAGUUCAUUAAUUUCUUGUUGUCUUCUGUUUUGCAGUUAGUUAAUGUUCCAUAUAAAGAAACUGUCAUGUGACACCAGUACCUCCUAAAAUUGGUCAGUGUGGUAGAUGGUUUAGAGAAAAAAGGAACCUGUUCCACAGGGCUGUGACCAUUCGAGGGAAGCACAUUCAAAGAUGUAGAUCCCCUCAGAGAAGUUUUCCAUUUCCCUGAAGUUAAAGAUCUUCAAAUGACUGCAAAUAACAUGAGGAUAUAUAGAAAAAUGCCCUUCCCCAAUUUCCAAAUCGUGAAAAUUUGGCUCAGCAGGUAAGUAUUUCUGUUUGUAGUUGUUUAUAAAACAGUGAAGACAUACCUUUUAAAAUCAAUCACAGUCCUUAGAUAAAUUCCUCCCAUUCUUCCUCCCCAGACUCCUAUCCAUUAAGAGUUGUGUCUCUGAAUUCAAAUUUCAUAAAACACUGAGUUCCCUUCAGAAGUAAAUAGUGCAUUUCCUAGGAGUGUCAUUGCCAACUGCAAAGACAGAGCAGUAUUUUUCAGUGUUGCAGCAUAGAGCCUGCAACAAUCUGGAGGUUGUGGCUGUGAUUUCAGUCUUUGGGGGACAAUUAGGAAAGUAAAGCUAAGGCCAAAGAUAAUUGACAUGUGGAAAGAGACAAAGGACAGUCCGAAUCUCGUAGGAGGAAGGGAGCGGUCCUGAGAGACCAGAGCUAGGCAGGCAGCUGUCGCUAAGAAUGGAACUUAGUGAUCUGCUGUGGGCCCAGAGCGCUCAGUGAGAACUCAGAGGACUAGGAAACAGGCUUGAUAGCAGUAUGACUUUUAAUGCUAAGCUCUGCCUUCUGGUGAUAUCCUGACCUACUCCAGCACUUCAGAGCACUCUAGGGUUUGAUCUCAGUAAAUAACUUGGAAAUGCAACCACCUUUUUGUUGGAAAGAAAGUAAUAAUGUAUCCGGAAAGAAAGCAGGUUGGAAAACACCAGUGUUUCCAAAUCUUUGAUAGAUUUGAAUUUGGGGAUUCAUAUCAUUGGCUGCUUUUCAGCCACAUGUGCUCACCUUUGUACCCCCGCCUACCCUGCCCCACCCCAUGAGGUUAAUGCUUCACACAGAAGGAUGGUAGAACGAAGUGGGGCAGUUUCAAUGAAAGGGAGCAUUAAGCUGAGCUCUGCCUCUUUCCUUUGUCUGCAUGUCUGGUAAACACAACUUAAUGGAUUGUGCCUCCUCCUUCCCCCAGUAUACUCCCAUGAAGCCCCUAAAGAAUAAGUUUAUCCCAUAGCAAUCUAUGGUAUGGUGUCAUAUUGGGAGUCUUGAGCUGAAAAGUACUUUCUCACGGUAUAUUGACGCAAGAGCUUCCAGCUGUCCAGAGCGCAAGAGCCAGCGCCAGUCCCCAGAGGGUUGCUAUGGGAACACUGUUAUGGCAACUGGUUUUCAUCACAGACUCUGCAGUUCCAUUGGCUGAACUAUAACCACACGCUAGUCCUUUAAUGGUUAACAGUAACUUUAAAAUCAUUUGAAAUUUAAAAAUAAUUUCUGGUGGUGUGGAAUAGCUAGGGAGGGCAGUGUGGCCAGCCGCGCAGCUAUGGUGUGAGCUGACCCCAUUCAGAAUAUUGAAAAACAUGCUCAUUUAAAAAAAGAAUGUAUUUUUACGUUGAUCAGAACAAUUUAUCAUGAAAGCAUUGAUUAUUUAUUUUUCCCCCAUUGUAAACUUUAUACAACUUGCUUAAAUGAAUCCUUGUGUUGCCUCUGCUGGUCACUCUCACUAGGCCACUUCCUUCUGUUGAGUCUCUUCUUCCCUCUCUGUAAGCACCAACUUCCUCAACUUUUUCUCACAGUGUUCAAGCUUAACACAUAAUUUUACCAAUGAGAGCAGCUGAGAAGUUUCGAGCUGCCUUUUGGUGAUCUCAGACUCUUUCACUGAGCUUCAGGCCGGGACAGUCAAGAGUCACUCCUGCAAUCCGCUGUCCUGGCCUUCCUUAACUCACAGUUUUACAACUUGCCAAAACUAAAUUGCCUUUGCGGUCAACUGCUUUUCCUUUCAGACUUAGGAGAUGUUAGGAACCAUGAGCGUUGCAGUCUGUGCAGUCUGCGCCUGCCUUUCUAAGUUUGGCCAUCCUGGGAAGUAGAAGUGUAAAAGCUGUAGAAUUUGAAACUUUUGGACCACAACUCAAAACAAGUGUAUGGAGACCCAGUAUUACAUGUACACAGGCACGUCUACCUGAAACAAAGUCACUGGCCGUACCAUGUGCAAGGCACAUUCUUAUGUUUUCUAAUCUGUUGUGUUUCUUUUUAAAAAUAUGCUGGUGGUUAUCCUCAAAAUUGGUUGACAACUCAUUAAUGUAUGGUGGUCAGCAGUUUGAAAACCACUGAUUUUUUUUUUGAAUUUCAAACUUUUAUGUUAAUUUCAGGGGUAUAUGUGCAGGAUGUGCAGGUUUGUUGCAUAGGUGAACAUGUGUCAUGGUGGUUUGCUGCACACAUCAUCCUAUCACCCGGAUAUUAAGCCCGGCAUCCACUAGCUAUUCUUCCUGAUCCUCUCCCUCCUCCCACCCGCCAUCCUCCAACAGGCCCCAGUGUGUGUUGUUACCCCUGUGUGUCCAUGUGUUCUCAUUGUUCAGCUCCUACUUACAAGUGAGAACGUGGUAUUUGCUUUGCUGUUUCUGUGUAAGUUUGAUAAGGAUAAUGGCCUCCAGCUCCAUCCAUGUCCCUGCAGAGGACAUGAUCUCAUUCCUUUGUAUGGCUGUGUGGUAUUCCAUAGUGUAUAUGUACCACAUUUUCUUUAUCCAGGCUAUCAUUGGUGGGCAUUUGGGUUGAUUCCAUGUCUUUGCUAUUGUGAAUUGUGUCGCAGUGAACAUACAUGUGAGUGUGUCUUUAUAAUAGAAUGAUUUAUAUUCCUUUGGUUAUAUACCCAGGAAUGGGAUUGUUGGAUUGAAUGGUAUUACUGUCUCUAGGUCUUUGAAAAAUUGCCACACUGUCUUCAACAAUGGUUGAACUAAUUUACACUCCCACCAAUAGUAUAAAAGCGUUCCUUUUUUCUCUACAACCUCACCAGCAUCUGUUAUUUUUUAAUUUUUUGAUAAUAGCCAUUCUGACUGGUGUGGGAUGGUAGCUUAUUGAGGUUUUGAUUUGCAUUUCUCUAAUGAUCAGUGAUGUUGAGCUUUUCUUCUUGUGUUUGUUGGCUGCAUGUAUGUCUUCUUUUGUGAAGUGUCUGUUCGUGUCCUUUGCCCACUUUUUAAUGGAGUUGUUUGGAAAACCACCGAUUAAAGCAAUUAUCAGUAGAAUUAAAGAAGGAAAUGACCUGUUAGAUGAAUCUAGGACAAAAGGACUAUAAUUCUUUUUUGAUUUUUUUUAAUAUGGAGAUAACACUUGGCUCUCAUUGUUAGUGUGAAAUUUAGCAGAUUAUAGAACCUACAGUACUUCAAAAUGCUAAAUACUUCUGCCGUAAUAUGUAAUUCUUAAGUUUAAAAUGAGGAGACGUCCAUAGAAGAACCGAGAACAGAAACUUGUAAGCCAUCUGUUAGAAAAUUGGCAGUAUGUAUAGCUGAUCACCUUGGGCUGGUUGCACAUUGUUGGAUAAAGCAAGAUUAAACAAGGUAUUACAAAAUAAAUGGGAGGUCAGUUAAAGUACGAGAUAGGUUUGGCUGGGUGUGGUGGCUCACGCCUGUAAUGCCAGCACUCUGCGAAGCCAAGGCGGGCAGAUCACUUGAGCUCAGGAGUUUGAGGCCAGCCUGGGCAACAUGGUGAGACCUCAUCUCUACAAAAAAUACAAAAAUUAGCCAGGUGUGGUGGCGCGCACGUGUAGUCCCAGCUACUUGGGUUGAGGUGGAAGGAUUGUGUGAGCCCAGGAGGUCGAGGCUGUAGUGAGCAGUGAUCACACUGCUGCGUUCCAGCCUGGGUGACAGAGUGAGACCGUGUCUCAAAAAUAAGUAAUAAAUUAAUUAAGUAUAAGAUAGGUUUGGGGCAAGAAUAGUUGCAAGGAGUCUAGUGUUACGCGUCAAGUGUCUGUUGAGAGGACAGUGGCUUGGCCCUUUGAAAAUUAUUUCCUAAGACUCAGUGCUAAAUUACAUUUCUUUUAAUGUAAAUUUUCUUAUUGGCAGUAUAACAUACAUACAGAAAAAUUACUAGAGUAUCACAUCAUGAUAGGUUUUUCACAAAGUAAACAUUUCACACAGUAAACAAAGUAACUAGCGCCCCAAUCAGAAAAGGUAAUUGUUAUUAACUCCCCAGAAAUCUCUUCAUGUCCUCUUCUAGUCAUAGCCAUGGUCCUAAUUUCUAACAUCAUAAUUUUUAAAAAAUAUCGGCGUGUAAUUCACAUACCAUCAGUUGUACCCAUUUAAAGUGUACAAAGGUUGUCAGCAUAUUCACAGUUACACAACCAUCACCACAGUCUUAGAACACUUUCGUCAUUCCAAAAAAGAACCCCGUUUGCCUGUGUUUAACAAUUUGCCUGUUUAUAAAUGGAAUCAAACAGUAUGUGCUUGACUUCUUUGGCUCAGCUUAGGGGUUCUGAUACUUACUCAUCCCCAAUGUGUGUAGUUGUGGUUUUUCAGUCUUGAUGCUGUGUCUCACAAUUUAUUCUACUGAUGAUGGACAUGUGAGUUGUUUCUGGUUUUUGCAUGGAUGUUUUAUAUGUGUUUCUUGGUGAAUAUACAUCUCUCUAUUUAUAUUCACAAGAAUAUAUACCAAGGUAUGAAAUUUCUGGGACAUAGGGUAUGUAUAAACUUGGCUAUUAGAGUUAUUGUCAAAGAGUUUUCCAAAGGAAAACCUUAUACCAGUUAACACAUUCCCACAGCAGGAGUUGAGAGUUCCAGUUACUCUGCCUCCUUGCCACACUUGAUAUAUCCUCUGUCAUUUUCAUUUUAGCCCUUCUGGUAGUCAUAAUGGUAUCACGUUGUGGCUUUAAUUUGCAUUUCUCUAAUGGCUAAUAUAGUUGAGUACCUUUUUUCAUAUGUUUAAUGGCCAUUUGGAUGUUAUCUUUUGUGAAGCUCCUGUUCAAUGCUUACUUUUGUCCAUUUUUCCCCUACUGAAUUGCCUGCUUUUUUCUGACUGAUUUAUAGUACUUUCUGUAUUCUGGCUAGAUAUCUGUAUUGCAAAUAAGCCUCCCACUUGGUGGCCACCCUUUGUGCCAGGUUACCUUUUAUGCAUUGGAGAAAUAAUCUUAUGACUGACUCAGAUAUUGACAUAACCUUUGCCAACUAUCUUUGCCCAAUAGAUUUUAUAAAAAUCAAAUCAUAUGUCAAGCUUAAAUAACAAUUCUUCCUCUUGUUUAAUGAUGUCAUCAUAGUGGCAUGUUUAAGAGUGUAAGAUUUGUGAGAAGAGGAAAUUAUGUGAAUGUUUGCACUUUUUUGUUAACUGUUGUAUUGGAUUAUUUCAUUUCAGAUAUGGCUGUUUUUGUUUUGCUUCUUUUGAUGUGCAAGUUCAUGUGCCAUAAAUGUGUGGUGUAGACACUACUAGUUACUUACGCAAUGUUCAUUCUCUCUCCUUCUCUACUAACAGAGCCCUAAUUUGUUUAGAACUGUAAUAUGCACAGUUAAAACAACUUGUCCUCUCAGGACCUUUUGCAGUUAGGGUUGGUCGUAUGACAUGGUCCUGCGAAGAAGAUACGGAUAGAAGUCUGUGGGUGAGUGGGACUGCCUGGAAACCUGUUGCUUUACUAAGAGAAAGAGACAGACUUAGCUGACAUACAUACUUUGUCCUUUGCCUGUGAUCAUGAUGCGUAGAUGCUUGGUGGCCAUCCUGCAAUCUUGACAAUGAAGAUGUGCUAAAGAUGGCAGAGCAGAAGAUAAAGCUUGGCUUUUCUUUUUUUUUUUUUUUUUUUAUGGCAUCAUGAAAUCAUUUUGUAUAAAACAUGAACUGCUUUUUUAAGGUUCUACAGAAAAACAGAAGAGAUAGGAGAUAGGGAGAAAGAGAAAGUUGUUGCGGGGGAGGGAGAGAGAUUUAUUAUAAGGAAUUGGUUGAAACAGUUAUGGAGGCUAAGUCCAGUGAUCUGUACCCCGCAAGCUGGAGACCCAGGAAAGUUGGUGGUGUAGCUCCCGUCUGAAUCCAAAGGCCUGAGAACCAAGAGAGUCAAUGGUGUAAAUUCUAGUCUAAGUCCAAAGGCCUGAGAACCAGGAGAGCUGAUGGUGUAAUUCCAGUCUGCAGGUGGACUGGAGCGUAGAGAGAGCUAAUUCUCCUUUACCCCAUCUUUUUGAUCUAUUCAGGCCACCAGUGGAUUGAAUGAUGCCCGUAUGCACUGAGAAGGGCCAUGUGUUUACUCGGUCUACCAAUUCAAAUGUUAAUCUCAUCCAAAAACACCCUCACAGAUACCUUUGGAAUGAUGUUUAACCAAAUAUUUGGGUACCGUCUUCCCCAGUGAAGUUGACACAAAAUUAACCAUCACAGCUGCCUUCCUGUGGGCCUCAUGUUAUAUGAGAACAGUAUUGGGUAAGUUGGGUUUCCAUUAUAUUCUGCUGAACUCAGUCCCCAAGCAAUGUAUGCAUUACUCAAACUUCUUGACCUUCAAAAUCAUCAAGUGACUUGUGGCAAGUGUGCCAUGGUGCUGAGGUCUUUGUUCAUUUCGACUGGAAUAAAAUCGGACUUUGCCACAUCCUCCUAAGAUAAAAUAGAUGUGAGAGCAUUUACUUGAAGUGGUUCUGUGGAUGUUGGUACAUUGUGAUUUCAGUUACAGAAAAGCCACAGAUGGAACUGAUGUUAAAAGCACCUCAAGGACAACCAGGUACUGGAGCAGAUGCCAAAAGGAGUUCUUCUGCCCUGUCAUCAAGAUUCUGAAUCACUCAAUUUAUUGGACAAAAGCAUUUAGCUCUGAUUCCUCUUGUGUUCUCUCCAAAUCUCCAUCAGAGUAAGAAGAGACUUUGAGAGAAUUAGUCUCUCUUCUGAGUAUCUGUUAUAGAUGUGAAAGAUACUUCAGAAAAUACAUGGCUCUGGUUUCAUCAUUUUGGGAAAAGCAGCUUGAUAUGCUUUGACUUGUUAUUACUACAGUUCCGUCUGAGAUGGCAACUCACGUUACACUAACGUGGGCCAAAAAAAAAAGUGCUUGUGUUUUUGUCCUUUAUAGAGUUUUUUAAAAAUUAAAAAGCUAAAAAUUAGUUUGUCUUAAAUAUUAUAGCAUAGAUUUUAGAGGUCUCUUUGAGAUUUUAGAACCUGUUAGUUCAUCCUUUGAUUAGGAAUUUCUAGCCAGGACUCAGGAUAAAGGUCCAAUUUCUGGUCAGUAGGGGCGCUGGUUGUGAGGCUGUUGUCUCAGCUCCAGACACAUCUUCAUACUCUGCUUUGUCAUGAGACUCUGCAAACCACAUCUUUCCUUUGCUGGAGAGCUUUUUGUUAGGGUAUACCAGGAUUGGACACGAGAGACUGGAACCUGGAGGCGGGAAGAAGGGAGCUCCCCCCUUCUAUUUGCUUUCUGUUUCUAACAACGAUGGCACAGCCGUGGUUUUCCAGAAGCUGAGCAGUGGCUGUUCACUCCUGAAGGAAUAGUGGGUUCCAGGGUGCGGUUUUCCACACUUGUAGAACCAGCUUCAUCUCUCCACUCAAAGAUCACCGCACCGUCAGCCGGUGGCGCCUCUUCAGAGGUUUGAAUCCGAGCUCUGUGGAGUCCCCACAUUUCUGAGGUACCAGUUACCAGGAGAGUGGUGUCCACGCCUGAGAGGUUUCACUCCCAGCUCCUGGAAAAGCUUCCACAUUUUAAUGAUCCCAGCCUUGCCUCUGGUUCCCAGCCCUAAGCGUGGCGGCUUCCUAUUGCAGUUAUCUCUGUGAUACCUGAGAGUCCCCUUUUUGCCUCCUACCUCUUCACUAUCUGUUGACAGUUGUUUGUUCAAUCAUCUCUCUUAGAAUAAUUGCUAUGGUCUUGGUCCGAGAUAUAAUAGGCAACCAGGUUUUCAGCUCCUGGAAAAGAGCCAUGAGACCCAGGUCCUCUUCUACGCAAUCCCAAGCUCAGGUGGAUUUUUCACUAGCUUUCCUCAAUACAACAUAGGGAUCCCUCCCUAGAUGAUGUGAUUCACCCCCGUGGGGAUAGCUGCGAGAUUAGGGGAAACUGAUGUUUUACCUACACCCUGGUCAUGAAGACCUUGCUUUGCUCCCUCCUUCAUUCCUACCCUGCUGUUCCUCAGUCUCCUCAAGACCUAUGUCCAAUCAGUCUGUUUUCUCCUACUUAAUAGCACCUUCUCAGCUUCCCUUUUCUUUUUAGUCAGUCUGGAUCCCAUUACCAUCAUUUCAGUCACCUUCCAGUCCCUUUUACUCUCACAUGUUUUUGUUGUCCUGCCACACCUGCUGACAACCCCAAGCCAGAGUCAUUCCAACCUCUCUCCUCCCAUGCUCUGACAUGAUAGUAGCUGCCCUGGAGGAAAUUCACAAUCUAAGCAUCCAAUGUCAGCUGGAUCCUCCCUGCCAUAGCUCUCCUGAUGCCUCUGCUCUAUCCUGAUCCUACCCUGCUGCCUCCUUUUUAUCUCACUUGGAGGGUGGCCUAACCUACCCUUCUCAUACAGCUUGAAUAUGGAGGCAAUCUUAAGGCCUCUUUCUACCUCCAAAUCUACCAGCAUCUUGUCUUACUUGAUUUGGAGAAAAAGCUGUUCCUCUUUCUGUCAUAGGCUAAAUCUUCCACUAUCCUGCUUUCUUAUCUAUUAUGUUAUCUAAUUUACUUUCUAUUGGCCCCCUCUACUUCCAGUGUAAUUAAGUCUUAUAAGGGCAGGGAAUUUGCAUCUGUUUUGUUUGUGCAGAUGUGAGGUGUGAGGAAAGGAAAGCUGAUGAAAAAGAAAGCUUGGAUGAUUCCCAGAUUUUUGGCCUGAACACUGGAAGGCCUGGAGUUGCCUGUAACUGAGCUGGGGAGGGCCAUUCAUUGGUGAGGUUUGGAGGGGACAGUCAAGAGUUUAGUUCAGGACAUGUUAGCACAUUAGACAUCCACGUGGGGAUAUUGGGUAGGCAGUGGAAUGUACAACUUUUAGAGAGGAGGUCUAGGAUAUAGGGAUAAAUAUCAGUCUCAUCAGCAUAAAGAUGGCAUUUAAAGCCAUGAGAGUAGAUGGGAACUUUAAGGAAUAAUUGUCAAUAAUAAAGGGAAGGAGUCUAAGGACUGAGCCCGGGGACACCAAUGCCAAGAAGCCAGGGAAGAAAAACUACCAAGGAGAUUGAAAAGGAGAGCCCUGGACUACGAUACCAGGUGGAAAACCAGGACAAUGUGGCAUCCUGACAUCCCAGUGAAGAAAGUGUUUCAAUGAAGUGUCCCACUUCUUCACACUCCAAAGUGUGGCUGGCAAGUGAUAUUAGAUGAGAACAGAGAAUUAACCAUUGGAUUUGGCAUUGCAGGGAGUCAUCGUUGACCUUGGCAAGAGUGGGUUUAGUAGAGUGGGGAGGGGUGAAAGCAUAAUUGGAGUGGGUUUGAGAGAAAAUGGAUAAAUGAAGGAGAAAACAAUUAGCUCGUGGGGAUAAAAAUUUAUGAAGAUAGAAAUGGGUUUCUGAUUUAAAAAAUCAAUCUUGGUGCCAUUAUAAUCCUAUGGGCUCUUGAAAUUACUCUCCACACUGUGUUAUUCUUCUGAAUGCAGUGCAGGUUCUUCAGCUUUGCUGGAGUACGUAUCGACUUUGCUGGGAGCAUGACUUUGUGCAAGGCAUAAAGGUUAUACCUCUGCAGCUCUUCUACUUUGUCUCUGCCAUCUCUGACCACUCAACUCAGGUAACCAAUGAGAGAUGCCCUGUUGAUCUCUUAUCCUUGGGAAUAAUUUUAAUCUCUUCCUCCUGUUUAAUGCUAGUGUCCUCCUUUCCCCAUAAAUGUGGUUGUGUGCCUGUUUGUCUCGUCCAUGAGAGUAAGCUUUUAAGAACUGGAACUCUGCACCAAAUGUGCAGUGAAAUGACUUUGUUGGAGACCCAUUGUCUGCCUGCUGGCCCUCAUCAGUGGUGACUUCAUAUUCCUCUUUUUAGAGAGUUUUACAUAGAGCCUUUUUGAAAUGGUAUCCUGGGAAAAUAAAGAGCUGGCUGUUUGUAAUACUUUCUACCAGGAGUGGGGUGUUCACUUUGUGUUCUCUAAUAAUUAAAUGUUCGGAAUCACCUUUUUUGGCACAAUGAAAGGGCAGAUAAACAGAUUGAUAGAUGAAGAGGUGAAAAGUAGGAAGCAGUGGGAAAGAAAUGGGAAGAGGAUCUUCCUAUCUACCAGUUGCUUUCAUGUGGUAGAGCUUAAUGAGAAGAUGAUACGCUAAUUUCCUGAGCUGUGACAUAUUUACAUGUAGAAGACUUACGUGAGGGCCCUUUGUCUUUUUUCAAGUGUAGAUGAUUUUGAGAUGGCCUGGUUGCUUCCCCAAGGAGAGGAGGCUUCAGGCUCUCCCACGGGCAGUUUUUAGGGUGUAGGAAGUAGAGAACACUCUCUUGAUGGGCUCACUUCCAGAUGUGAUUCUCAGUGGAUUGUUUUCCUUUUCGGCAGCAUCAACUAGCUCUAGUGGCCAAGGCUUCUGUAAGGCUUCCCAUCCAGGAGUUUUUCAUGCAGGGAUGCUAUUGGAGGCCAGACUUCCAGUUUUGCUAGGAGGAGAUGCCUAUUAAGUUAGGGGGCCAGGGAUUCGAUUGCAGCAGUCACUACUCAAGUCAGUCAGUCACCAUUUCAUCUGUAAGUCAGGGACUCUUUGUACUUGCAGUCCCCAUAGGCGCUUGGCUCUCGUGAUGUGAUUUAGAGAGUCAGUGGCAGGGUUUGAGCUGCAGUGUGAGCACAGAGGAUUAACGGUAGUCACAGAGAGCCUGAGCAGCCUGUGUGAGUGACCCUCUGCAUCCUACAUGGAAUGAGGGACAACAUGGAGAGACUAAAGACGAUCCCUCAAAGCCUAGCUUCCUUCAUUGCUCCUGCCGUGGACUGUCUUGCAGGGACAGUACACAUGCUGGCACAUAUUACACACAGGGAGCCGUUUGCAGUGAAUAGUGAUGCAAAGGCUGAGAUAGUAUCCUCAUAAAGAUUGACCUCUAAUCUCAAGUCCUUUUUUGUAGUAGCAGGAAUACAUAAUUUAGACAAUAUUAUCUUGCACAGUUAACAGAAGGAAACUAGAAUAAGAGGGAAUUCACCUCAGCUGAACAAACCAAGCUUCUCUGUAUCAUCUAGCAAGCUCAUAAAAAUGCCAUCUAUAGAUUGACUUUAAUAAAGGAGCCCACUGAGGACACAAGCACCUGAAUUACAGAUUCCCAGUGCACACGCAAGCAUUUAUCGCUGACAGACAAAGGAACAAAAUCUCCAGGAGGCAGCUGGGAUCUUUUCAUUUUGAAAAUGCUUUAAUAAGUGUUGACAACACUGUUUUGCAAAAUGUAAAGGUACUAUACAAAUUCUUAAUACAAAAAGAAUAAAUUAAAAGCAGAUUUCUUUUUUUAAUUCUGCAACUUUGUCUACAACGUACAUCUUUUUCAUUGAUUACAGUUGAACAGAAUCCAGUAAAAUCAUUUUACAUGCUCUACAGUCAGUUUCAGGAGCAACCUAAUCUUUUUUCCCCCAUUAUUAAACUAGAGUCCAUUUUACACAACUUGUAAUAAACUAUUGACAUUAAUGUAUAUGUAAAACUUUACACCUAGUUAACUAAGCAGUAACUGGUCAUCUGAUAGCACCUGGAUGGGGUUUGCUAUAUUUAGAACUAAACUAAUACUGAAUGAAAACAAAUUGGAAUUUUAACAGUUUCAACACUCACCUGCAUAUAAUAAAAUAAAAAAUCAACCUGGCUCACAACAUAGUCUGAUGUAUGUGUUUUCACCAGUCUUCUGGCUGAAACAGGCAAUUUCUUUUACGCAUCCGAAGAAUCCAAUAGGGGCUUUAUAUCAGACCAAGGACUUCGUAUUUCACCUUAUUUUGUUUUAAAGAAAUAGGGAUAAAGAGUUUGCAAGUGCUUGUGUACAAUAACUACAUCAUUUCCCACCACACUGAUCAUUAAUCAUGUCAGUCUCAAAGGACUAACGUUUUAUGUACAUUUUGUAUUAACUGAACUCAGCUAAACAGUAAAACCUGUUUUACUUAAUCUCUGUCUUGACUACCAGACUAUCAUGAUGUUUGUUGGAACUGUAAUUCCUGCUCUCCAUUUCUCUCUGUCCCCCAAGUUGAAAAUAUAACCCAAAUCUUUAGAAUUUUUGCCUCUCAUUCCUUGCAACUCCAGUGGGCUAGAAUCUUGAUCCAGUUUUCUCCAGACUAGAUUUCAAGCUACUAUGCAUGAUGUAGAACAUGUAACCAUGUAACCUCAUCAGCUACCUUUUCCCUUUUGACUUUUCCUGUUGCACACAGUUCAGUCUGACUAUCCAUGAAUCUUCUUUGGGAGAAAGAAAAAUGGCCCAAUGUAUAAUGUUUCUGAAUGGGGAAGGGAGAAAAAAAAAAAAUCACUGUUCUUUGUAGCUCUAACCAUGAAAGUAAAAGCAACAAAAAUAUCCCCCAGUGAAUCCCUAGAAUCAUUUAAUAAUGUAACCGGUAUCUCUUUAUCCUGCAGGUGUACACUUAAAGCGUUCUGGGAAUAUGAAUCCCUUCUGCACCCUGGAAUCACCAGUCCAGCCAUGCAUGGAGCUGGGGAAAGCAGGCCCUGAAUUGUCUAGAGAGACUUGGUGGAGGAGGCCACGGCCCGCCUUGUCCCUGCCGGGUCCCGGCCAGGUGUGUGUGUGCCCCAGCUCGACUCUCGGUGGUCUCCAGGCUGCAGCAGAAGGAAUACCUUGGUAUUUGUUUCAUUUUAGUGUCCAUCCUUACCCUUCUGGUCUGGUAGAGCCUAUGGUUAUUCUUGGAUUCCACAUACAUGAAAAGCGAAGAUUUUUCUUUGUUUUUAUGCUUAAGCUAACUUCAGUUCUGCUUUCCCACAAAACUACCCCCACCCUGGCUCCUGUCCCUGGCUGUCAAUGCCUUUCCAAUAGGAAGUCAUUAGAGUGAGAAAAAAAUUCCACCCCCACCCCAUCCCCCCACCACUUGCGCCAAAAGCACAGCAUACCACCUCUGCGGAAACCUUUUUGUGCCAUCUUGAAUAACCCAACUAAAGUCGUGCACUUGUUACUAUAAAAGUAUUUUUGAGGCCUUUGAAGAUUGAUGGCUUUCCAGUUGUGUUUGAAGCAUAGCUCAAAACAUGUAAACGUGCAGCUCCCACACAUUAAUUUUUUUCUUCUUUCCUCCUCUUUUGGUAUCUGCACACAAAUGUGGUGCAUGACAGUAACUGAUGAUGUAGACACAUGGGCCCUUUGGGAGCUGAUAUUUUUUUCAACCCUGCUCUGCCUGUUGGCUAGUAGACACACGAGUCAAAUCUUUCUACCUAAGGGCAUAGUUGGGUUCUUGGAAUAAGUGACACAUAGGAGAAGUCGGAUCUGAGCUCUUUUGUCACACAAGUGCUAACGAACAGAAAAUGAGCCACGACAGUUAAACACUGAAUGGAUCGCAAUGUGCUUUUCCCUUGGUUUCCCAUAAAAACGAAAAUGAAACACCUUGUGCAAAAAAAUAGGAUACGCUUUUACUGGUUGGUUUAAUGAGAGAGAACCACUUUUGGCCAUUAUCACCUUACGUUACUACAAAUCCUGAAAGGAAAGCAGCUUUGAGUCUUGGGCUCGGCUGAACCCCCUGCAUGGACCGGGGCUAACAGUACCCUCUACGACUCCCACAGGUCUCUCUUUGUGUCCAGAUGGAUGGCGACUGUGAGUCAGCAACGCCAGCCAAGACUUCCUCGCCUUUACCGUGGCAUUGGGGCAGUUUUUCAGGCUCUCUACGGAGAGAGAAGUGGGCCAGUAAGGGAGAGGGCUAGAGAGAGGACACCAGUUUACAUAGGGUUGACUUUCACUUGUGUGUAGUAGCAGUUCAGAAUUUAAAAGAAAUUUCCUUGCAGAAAGAAUGUCUUCCUCUUGGCCCCUCUUAAUUUUUUAUGUUUUUAUUUAUUUUUAAUCUUUGGCAGCAUAGAACUGAUUGUGGUCCUCCGAUGCAUUUCUGGUGUCGAGAACUUCCUUUCUCAACCUCCCCUUCCCCCAUAGCCAUCCCCACAAGCUGUCCCAUCAAGGAAUAUUUCAGGUGUAAACUGAAUAUGCCACGAGGCCUCCUCUUCAUGAAGUGCUUGGUUGGCCUACGUAUGGGUGGCAGGCUGGACACAGCUGAAUCGUCUUUCUGGGUCACCCUGUAACUCAAGUCCCCUUUCCCGUUCUCUCCCAACGCUACUUAUCCGCAGGAAUUGGAUGCCGGCUGGCCCCCCUGAUGGUUCCUGGCCUAGGGGCUGUCAUGGCAGAGGGAAGCCACCAAGGUGCCAUUGAGGAUUGGUGUCUGGCUCUCUAUGGGCAAGAGCGCCAGGGGACACACAGUGGGACCGGAACCUUCCAGAAUGUCUCCUCAGUCAGGUUUUCAAGGGGGAGGGAAUGCGGAGACAGGAGAAAAAAAGUGCUGAGGGCCAAAGCUGGUGCAGGGUGACGGUGCGUCUGGGUAAGGCAAAUGAGAGGCAGUGAGGUGAUCUCAGAAUGGCGUUGAGGCGGUCAGAUUAGGCCGGGCUGGCUCACACGAGGGUCCCGGGCUUGGCUUUUUCCUGCCCGUACCACUGGACAUCAGCUAGUUCUGGAUAGAGGGAGGAAUCCAGGAAACAGCUAUCAUUGUAGCUCCUGUGGGAGGCCCAAGAAAGGAGAUGAGACAGUUAGUUAGUGGAGGAGGAUGGGUUCAGCCAGGCCUGCACUGAGAAGGAUAUGUUCACCUUGACAGGGCCCUGUGCUAAUCACGAGUCUUUCCUGUUCGGAGCAGUGAGGCCUGAGACCCUCAACAGUGCUGUGUGUACAGAAGGCCCCCAGAAUCCACACAAAGGGGCCGCCUGAAACCUAGAGCAUUUGUGAAGGAGGAAAAUGGAAGGUAACUUACUCAGUGCGGUGGUUCUUCAGCGUGGCUGCAUCCGGGGAGCACCUGGGAACUCCCAGAAAUACUCAUGCCUGGGCCCAAUUGAUUUGGGGUGUGUUUGAGCGCUGAGAACUGUCAAAGCUCCCCACCAGGUGAUUCUCAGAUGCAGCCAAAGCCAGAACCUCUGGGCUUUCCUCAGGGGACUUUUCCCACACGACAGCUGCCCGGGUUGUCCUCCGUGAGACCCCAGGGCUAACAGAUGUCACUAGGAAAUUUUUAUUCUGUCCUGGAAGAACAUUCAAAAUGUGAGUUUUCCCUAUAGUGAAACUGCGGUGGUAUUUUGAAUUGUGUUUUAAAAGUUUAAAAAAAAUCAAUGAUGACUUUGCUUUAUUCUAAAUAACAUGCAUUGUUUUGUGAUUAUAAAAGUGUGUUCAUUUAAAAUAGGAAAGUCUAUAGAAGAAAAUAAAAGGCUUUUUUUUUUUUUUUUAAGUAUUUUAGGGAGGUAUCACCAUUUAGGUUGGGUAGAAGUAAUUCUUAAAUCUUAAGAAGCAAUCAUAGAUAUGUGGAAGCCAAUAGUCAUUACUAGGGAUCAUGAUUCGGAAAAACAGCCUCUCUUCAAUGAUCCUGAAUGAGCCCUUUGAAUUCCUCUCCUGCAACUGAUCUCCCCAUGGGGAGUGGUGAGGGAUGGGUGACAGGAAGGGACCCUAACCCAAAGUAGUUCAGAGCGGGUGAGUUUUAGGAGCAUUUCGGUACCAAACACAGCUUCACGAUUGAGAAUCAUCAGUCAUCCCCAGCUUUCUAUUUCAUUUGCUAACCUCUCUAGGAACAACUGGAUGUUGUAAAUGUUUCUCAUCUGGCCUUAAAAUCCAUGAAAGCUGGAAAAUCACAAGGCAUCUGUGCAUAUACUGGUGGAUUUUAAUGAGAGUCCUGUGUUUGGAGCACCAGAAAUAAACCAGCUUCAGAAGCAAAGUAAGAAAAGGCCCUUGAUUAUGACACUGGCCAUGGGUAUUACUAUAUGUAGGUGGUAUGUGGAUGAUUCUGGGACACCUGUCCUGCAAACUUUGUCUCCACCCUAAGCUGACUUUUGACAUUGUGCCUGACUGAAAAACUUCUAAUGGGAGAGGUGGUUGGGCCUUGCAGGGGUCCUAUGUUUUUCUUAGGGGGACAGUCUCUCCCUAACUCCACGUGGUCCUGGUGGUGCUCUCCACCAUGGCGCCAUCCUCACUCCCGUGGGGGCCAGGGGACAAGGAACCCAACGGGGCCGGGCCAAUGAGAGUCCCCCGAUCAAAAUCCCUGGUUCAAAGGUGGCCACGUGCCUGAGCAGCUUUGAAACCACAAGGAUGUCAUUUCCUCCUGAGAACUAGGUUAACAGGAGGAGGAAGCAGAGCUAGAGAUGGAAGGAGACCCAGCCAGCCCGGGCUCCAGUGACAUCGGCUGGUACACGCUUUUGUUUGCUUACGCUUGUUGAACUGAGUUUUUCAUAUGUAACUAACGAAUACUGGCACAUGUAAGUAGUUUCUUAAACUGUUGAUGAAAUUUUUGUUUCUAACACAAACAUGAUCUGGGUCUGUUUGGGAUAAAACUUCCCUAAGGGGUUUCAUGAGAUCUUAGGAACACUUAGCCAGUGUUUCCCAAAGUAGUCCUGUGAGUUGCUCUGAGGGGAAAAAAAGCUUCCAUGGAUAAAUAAAUUUGAGGAUUCUGCCUUUCAGAGGCCUGAAAUGUAAAUGUAUAUGAAACAUAUAUUAAAGGUUCUGAGAAGUCCUGGAUUAGUUUGCCACAGAACUUCUGGAACAGUAUCACCUAUUAACAUCCACAGAACACACUUUGAAAAAUACUCUUAAAUGGGCUAAUAUUAUGAAAUGUAGUUGACUCUCUUGUAUGUUGGAUCCUAAACAGUUUCUGGUUGAAACUAUUAAAGUUGAGUCAUAAUUGUGACAACAUAAUCUGCUUCAGAGGGACUAAAAGUGCACUAUGUAUUGAUCAUAAAGGCUCAAGAAAGACCAUUGAGUUCAAAGCAGUGAUGUUUGGAUCAGGCAGUAGAUGAGGUUAAGGGUUCCUGUGGUGGUUUAUUUGGUAUGUGAAGAGCCUAACUGUUGGCUGGCCCAUGGUGUUCUCCUGUGGUUCAUUAUGGAGGCUUCUGGGUCACAGAACCCACAUAUGAGAGGGCAUCGGGAGGAUCUGGAUGAUGGGGUGGGAGAUGCUGGAUUGGUGGUUUGGUUCUCAGGUGGCUCCUAGAGGAGCCGCAGUAUGGAAACCACUGGCCUGCUCCUGCCUCUGAGAAAAUGAAGCUGGAGGAAAAGAUGUAAAGAUGUAUUUUUUCCAAACUUGCGAUGUUUUAUACAGAAUCUUUCUUAGUGCUUCCACAUAGUUAUUGAAGUACGUAAGGUAUUUUUAAAGCUAUAAAUGUUGCUUCAUGUAUUGGUCUUUUAUUCUCAAGUCUGGGGAAGAGACCCUUGUUCUGGCUGCUCAGCUAAGCCUUUGCCUUUCAGUACAAAUUCAAUUUUCCGGUAGUAGUCAAGGAAUGCCAUGUGCUACGAAAGAGACCCUUAGGAAGCAUUUAUUCUUCACAAAUAAUACAAAUGGGGCCACUAAAUAGUUGCCCUAGUAAAAACCUAAAAACCUAAGUCAGUCAUUCACUGGAACAUGAGCUGGGGCAGGAUGAAGAUCUAGGUGUGCUCUCUCAACUGUGACCCAGAAGAGCAGCUUAGCCCUGGGCAGUCUGGGUCACAGCAAGUGGUGACUUCAGAAUCUGUGGGGGCUUUCCACUGCAAGAAUGCCCUUUCCCAGGGCUAUGCUCAGAGAUGUGUGGCCUGCAAAGGGUACUGGCUAAGCCAGGGCCGUCUGAUACCAGACAGAUGGCAAAUUCACCCACAUCUCACAGGGUUUUGUGGUUUAUAACUGCUUGGCAUAGGGAGGUGGGGCUGCUGGGAGGGAGGAAUUUCAAACUGAAUUAUUUUUUUAAACGUAUAACUAACUUACAGAACCAACUGGUGGCACAUACUGGGGUUGUUGAACAGUCCCACAGUUGGUCACAAGGCCAGAGGAUAGGGGAUGAGGCCCUCUAGAGGCAUCCUGUCUUACCUGGUCUGGGAAGGUGCUGUUGCUCAGUAUAAUGUAUGUGUGUCCCUGCAUGUGCACAUGUAUGCAUGAGCAUGAACUCGUGUAUGUAUUCGUGUAUGUAUGUAGGUAUUUCAAGCAGUGCCUACAUUCCCACCGCAGCUCUUUCAAACCUGGUUAAUUCUACUUCUGGCUGUCAGCCCUAUCUCCAUCACCUUUAGCAGAUGAUCGCCCUCCCAUACCGGGGGAGAAAAAGGCCAUUCUUCCUACUUCAAAAAUACUGCUCUCAUGACAUCACCCUGGCACUGGGGCUGGGGGAGGGGGUCUACCUUCCUUCCAAAGCCUAAGUCCCUGUCCUAAUUGCCCAUCUGUCAACUUUGCAAUAUUGUCCUAACUUACUUUUCAAAAGUCCAGUUUUUUCUCUACAGGAAACAAGACUCUCUACUGUUAACCACCCCUCACCCUUAUCUGUGCAUCCAUGUUUUUGCACUUGGGAUGGUCUCUGUCUCCACCUGUCUAAGCCCCCUCCUCCCACGGCAGGCUUCUGAGCCAGGCUCACAUAACAUCUCCGUGAACUCGAAAGUGACCCCCUCAUUUCUGAAUCCUCUCAGCAUUGCAUUUUGUUUCUAAGUCUUAGAGCACUUAAUACAUAAGUGUAGCAGUUUCUCAUGCUCCUUGUAUAUCUUCUGAUAGGCAAUUUGAUUUCAAGCCCUUGUGUCCCAGUUAGACUGUAAGGGUCCUGGGGCUAGGAACCAGACCAGGUGGUACUGUUAUCUGCCCCUGUGCUUUGCAGAUUUCGACGUGAAUCUUGUUAAAUGCACAUUAGGUUCAGUAGGCCAGGGUGGUGCCCGGGAGACUAGCUUUCUAACGAGCUCCCAGGUGAUGGUGGUAGUGAUAAAAAUGUUGGCUUAUGGACAUUUGGAAAAGCAGUGCUCAUAGCUUUUGGUACUCAGCACAGCUGUUACUCAAGAAUGCUGGGGGUGCUUCUGGAGCCACUGAGUCGGCCCUUGGUGCUUUGAAACUUACAUUGCAGUGAUGCUGUUCUUUUCAGGGACACUGAUUACUCACAGUAAAAUGUCUACAAAUCUUUGAAUGUAGAUAGAACAUGGUGAGUCUAAAAUAUACUUUGGGGCCAGGCGCACAGAUCACUUAAAGCUUAAAGUCAGGAGUUUGAGACUAUCCUGGCCAACAUGGCAAAACCCCGUGUCUACUAAAAAUACAAAAAUUAGCCACGCAUGCACCUGUAGCUACUAGGGAGCCAGGAGAAUCGCUUGAACCUGGGAGGCAGAGGUUGCAGUGAGCCGAGAUCAUGCCACUGCACUCCAGCCUGGGCAACAGAACAAGACUCUGUCUCAAAACAAAACAUACUCUGGGGGUCUUUUCUGGGAAGCAGUGUUAGGAAUAUCAUAAUUUUGAUGUAAGAACCUUCAGCUAAAAACAUAGUUCCAGUUCCCCAUGUAUCUAGAAAUAAGGCAUAAAUACAGCAUUCAGAUGUAUCCUUGUGGAAAUGAUGACAUGGACAAAAGCAACACAUGUGGGACCACAGACUCAUGGGCAGUAGGAACAAAACUCCCCUUACGGUACCUCUAUUCAUCAGUACUUUGGUGAGGUGGAGACUCAGACCCAUCCAGAAUGGGUGAGUUUUCUGUUGCUUCUCUGAACAAAGGAAAGCAGGAGGAGGAAGAGAAGAGAGGUCAUGUUACAGAGAGACACUGACACAGACACAGACACGAUUAGUAGCUUAUUAAUAUAUCCGAAAGGCUUGCUGAUUAGACACCUGAGUUAGCAACAGAUCAUACAAGUCAUGCAGUACUUUCAGUCCCCAUAAUUGAGUCAAAAUACCUAGUUUGUUAGGAGGGACGGGCCCUCUUUUACCCAUGGCCUCAUUUUGUAUCACAUCAUAGCAAACAGUUUAUGCCAAGAACCAAAAUUGCUGUUUUUCAAAUUUGGCUUGAGUCCUCACUAGUUGUAGGUGGUGAAAUAGGCAGGUUUCAAGACCAUCUUAAGUGCAUAGGACCCUGAGGAGGGCUUGUACAUUUCGGAGCCUGUUGACAGCCAAAUAAUACAAUCAAUCAUAUAUUUGGAUCAGGUGAGACUGGGCAUGAUUCAGAAAAGUUGGAAGAUCUAGAGAGGGAUCUUGCAAUCUGAAGUUUCUUGUUUAGUCACUGGAGGUAUGUAUUACAUAUAUGAAAGAUGUGUCAUUCUUUUAUGAGUUAAUCUUAGACCCCAAACCUUGCAGAGGCUGCCUGGCCAAACAGGUGAGAGCUGGGGUGUGGGUGGGUGAGUGUUAAUGAUCUAAAGGACAAAGGGGCAGCUACUGUCCAACAGACAGCCCAAGAAGUAGGAGCAGACACAGGAACACCGAGCUGGGGCUCCAGUUUCUCUUAUUUUAAAAGGAAUCAGAGGCAGCAGGGGAUCGUUCAGUGGUUGUCAAAACUUGAGUGUGGGUCAGCAUCACCUGGAGGGCUUAUCAGAAUGCAGCCUGCUGGGCUCACCCCCAGAGUUUUGGAUUUUUUUUGUGUUACAGGUAAGCCCGAGAAUUUGCAUUUCUGACAAGAUCCCAGGUGAGGCUCACUCGUGCUGCUGGCUUUGGGAUCACACUUAACUACCGGUAUAGUGGGGAAAGACAGGGUUUGGGGUCACAGAGGGCAGAGCUGGAAUUCCAGCUCCCUCCAGCUGUCAGACUUUGGGCCAGGCACUUAGUUCCUCUGAGCCUCAUCUAUGAAACGAAAACAUCUGGGUAUUUCCCCCGCAAGGGGAUGAUGAGGAUUGUAUGAGCUCAUGUGUGUUAGAAGCUGCUCGCAGCCUUUGAGUACACAGCAAGCACUCAGUAAGUGUUAGGACCCUUUCUUGCCAAAAAUGAAGGCUCCAGAAAACCUGGUGUAAAAAAAUUACCACAGAUAAACCUGCAGGAACAAAAAUGCCGACCAGGUGCCUGUAAUCCUAGCACUUUGGGAAGCUGAGGUGGGUGGAUCACCUGAGGUCAGGAGUUCGAGACCAGCCUGGCCAACGUGGUGAAACCCUGUCUCUACUAGAGAUUAGCCAGGUGUAGUGAUGCACACUAGUAAUCCCGGCUACUAGGAAGGCUGAGGCAGGAGAAUCACUUGAACCAUGGAGGUUGCAGUGAGCUGAUAUCGCACCACUGCAGUCUGGGCAACAGAGUGAGACUCCGUCUCAAAAAAAGGCCAAGUAUGAGAGCCUGAAAGGCAGACAAUACAGCCAAUUCUGGAAUUGUGCUUUUCUCAUGAUUCAACUCACAGCCAGUUGUCAGGUUUUCCCAGACAUCCCCCUGAUGCUCCACCAAACCAGGAACCAGACAAACCGAGGAAGGGGCCUCCUUAACUCCUCUAACCAACAGAUGAGAUGUUGACAGAACCUAACAUCUACUUAGAGAUGAUGUCUCAGGGGCAACAGAAGAGGCAGGUGCUGUAGGGCCAGGCGGGUUACCUGUGUCUGCCAGACCCUCCAGUAGUUCAGAAUAGCCUCACUGGCGCCGAGAUGAUAAUGCUGUAUGCAAACAUGUCAAGCUAUCAAAGGGAGCUGCCUUUCGGUUUCAUUAAUUUUGUUGUGUGCAGCUUCCACUGAAGGCUUCAGGGCACCUGAUCUCUUUUGUGUGUUGAGAAAGAGCAAGUGCUUGGCCAGGACACAGCCCUUUUUCUUGCACCCUGAGACAUCCUAAGACACUGGCUGUUUCACCUGCCCCAGUGUAUUUGCUGUCUUCAUCAGCUCUCUUUCUCCCCCUGACAUUCUUGCCUGGCAUUUUGAGUCAGCCUGAGUAUAAUCCAAACCGAAAUGAAAUGCUGUCUGGAAAUCUUACCAAAGAAGCACAGUCCCACUUCGUGCUUCCAUCUCCCCACAUCCCAAGGACCACCGCCUACUUUAAGAGAACACAGACAAUUCACCUCUAUAAAGGCACAGCCAGGAAAAGGAGUAGGCAGAGGUGACAGCAGAUCAUGGGGCUUCUCUUGAAAGGAAGACACCUCCCAGUGAUGAACCCUCAUCAUCCAUUUACUGACAUAUCCUUAUGUCACCAGGAUCUGAACGUCUAUGACACUCUUUCGAGCUGACACAGUGAAGAACAUAGAAGGAGAACUCACCCAGUCUGCCAGGGUCACAGAAUGAUCAUACUCAAGAUCUUCCUGGGGAGUCAAUGGCAAAUUUCACUGGGCUAUUUUACAGAUGAAGAAGGAACAUAAAGAAGGUUCUGGGACCCCGAAGUCCACGGAACACCCACCAUUACCUGAUCUUUGGAGCUUGUCAUUUGGCCAGUGGACCCUAAUAAACGUCCACGGGGAUGUGGGGAUAGAAUGCCAGAGCCUGGCUCGCUAGGGCAUCCAGGUUCUUCCUUCCUCUUUGCCCUGCUGUCUCCAGGCACCAAGAAUCUCCUACAGUUCCCCAAAGAUGAACCCCCCAUUAUCUCAGGUCACUCUGUUUCCCCCGAUCUUUACCAAAUUCCUGACUCAGAGUUCCUCCCAUUUGCUUCUGACUCUCAUUUUAUUCUUACCUCUCAUUUUAUUCUUAUGAUGUUUACCAUUUCUCUUCUCCUCAGUGUCCCUCUCUGAGUGGUAAGAGUAUGUUAAUAAGCCAGUGCUGAGACCGGAGCACGAGGCAACUGCUCAAUGUUGGUCAUUGUCACUGUUAUUAAAUGUAACUUAAGGGAA